GACUAUCCGCUGGGCGGGGUCGGUGCUGGCCGAGGGGGCGCCGGCUGCCGGAGUGGACAUGGCGGCCGGCCCCAUUAGGGUGGUGUUGGUCCUUCUAGGGGUGCUCAGUGUCUGUGCAGCCAGCGGCCAUGGGUCCGUAGCGGAGAGGGAGGCCGGCGGGGAGGCGGAGUGGGCGGAACCGUGGGAUGGCGCGGUUUUCCGGCCGCCCUCGGCGCUGGGCGCAGUGGGGGUGACGCGCAGCUCUGGGACGCCGCGGCCAGGGAGGGAGGAGGCGGGGGACUUGCCGGUACUGCUGUGGUGGAGCCCAGGGCUAUUCCCCCACUUCCCGGGAGACUCGGAGCGCAUCGAGUGUGCGCGCGGCGCGUGCGUGGCGUCCCGGAACCGCCGAGCGCUGAGGGACUCGCGGACGCGCGCGCUGCUCUUCUACGGCACAGACUUCCGCGCGUCGGCCGCCCCGCUGCCGCGCCUGGCGCACCAGAGCUGGGCGCUCCUCCACGAGGAGUCGCCCCUCAACAACUUCUUGCUGAGCCACGGCCCGGGCAUCCGCCUCUUCAAUCUUACCUCCACCUUCAGUCGCCACUCGGAUUACCCGCUGUCGCUGCAGUGGCUGCCCGGGACCGCCUAUCUGCGCCGCCCGGUGCCUCCGCCCAUGGAACGCGCGGAGUGGCGCCGCCGCGGCUACGCGCCGCUGCUCUAUCUGCAGUCACACUGCGACGUGCCAGCGGACCGGGACCGCUACGUGCGCGAGCUCAUGCGCCACAUCCCGGUAGACUCCUACGGGAAAUGCCUGCAGAAUCGGGAGCUGCCUACCGCGCGGCUACAGGACACAGCCACGGCCACCACCGAGGAUCCAGAGCUCUUGGCUUUCUUGUCCCGCUAUAAGUUCCACUUGGCCCUGGAAAAUGCCAUCUGUAACGACUACAUGACAGAAAAACUGUGGCGUCCCAUGCACCUGGGCGCUGUGCCCGUGUACCGCGGUUCUCCCUCUGUGAGGGACUGGAUGCCGAACAAUCACUCCGUCAUCCUGAUUGAUGAUUUUGAGUCUCCUCAGAAGCUGGCAGAGUUUAUUGACUUUCUGGACAAGAAUGAUGAGGAGUAUAUGAAAUACCUGGCAUACAAGCAACCUGGGGGCAUCACCAACCAAUUUCUUCUGGAUAGUCUGAAGCAUCGGGAGUGGGGAGUGAAUGAUCCUUUGCUGCCUAACUACCUCAACGGCUUCGAGUGUUUCGUCUGUGACUACGAACUGGCUCGGCUGGAUGCCGAGAAAGCCCACGCGGCCUCUCCCGGGGACAGCCCCGUCUUUGAGCCCCACAUUGCCCAGCCCUCACACAUGGACUGCCCAGUGCCCACACCUGGCUUUGGCAAUGUGGAAGAGAUUCCUGAGAAUGACAGAAAAGAACAAGAGGGAAGACAGACCUUCAGGCUGGGUGCAGUGGCUCAUGCCUGUGAUCCCAGCACUUUGGGAGGCCAAGGUAGGAGGAUCGCUUGAGCCCAGGGAUUCAAGACCAGCUUGGGUAACAUGGUAAAACCCCAUCUCUACAAAAAACAGAAAAAAUUAGCUGGGCAUGGUGUGUGUGCCUUGUAGAUCCAGCUACUUGGGAGGCUGAAGUGGGAGGAUCGCCACUGCACUCCAGAAACUAAAAAAAAAAAAAAAAAAAACCUUCAAAAAUAUAUCUAAGCCAGAUGUGAUGGCAUGGGUCUGCAGUCCCAGCUACUCAGAAGGCUAAGGCAGGAAGAUCGCUUGAGCCCAAGAGUUUGAGGCUGUAGUAUGCUGUGAGUGCGCCUAUGAGUGCCAACUGGGCAACACAGUGAGACCUCUGUCUAAAAAAAAAAAAAAAAUCUGUUGGGCUGGGUGAGCUGGCUCACGCCUGUAAUCCCAGCACUCUGGGAGGCCAAGGCAGGCAGACCACCUGAAGUCGGGAGUUCAAGACCAGCCUGACCAACAUGGAGAAACCUCAUCUCUACUAAAAAUACAAAAUUAGCUGGGCGUGGUGGCGCAUGACUAUAAUCCCAGCUACUCAGGAGGCUGAGGCAGAAGAAUCGCUUGAACCCAGGAGGCGGAGGUGGUGGUGAACCAAGAUCACGCCAUUGCACUCCAGCCUGGACAACAAGAGCAAAACUCCAUUUCAAAAAAAAAAAAAAAAUCUGUUAAAAUUUGAUAUAGUAGGCACUGACAAAAGAGGUCAAAUGCAGGACUGAUUUCUAAGCUUGCAAUCUAUCUAAAUGCAGAUGCUAAUUUAGAGUGCAUAAUUAUUACACAAGUACAGACCUAGGUUAGGGCUUAAAUUUCAUUAUGUGCAAUAAAAAGGUUAAGUGAUGGUUAAGCAAGGUGUAGAUUAUCCUUACCUCUCCUAAUGACAUGGGCUCACAUUGGCAUUCCUUUCAUACUUUUACGUAUAAAGUGGGCAGUUGUUUCUGAAUGACUGUUGCUGGAGCCUCAGGCCUGCUUUGUGCUUGGUGCUUUCCAGACUUUCUCCUUUAUUCCUAUCACCAUAUACGUACUCACAAAAGAGCAGUGUAAACCAGGUAUUACAUUUCCACAAGGGAAAGUAGAACCAGGAAUAGCCACAUGAUACUUACCGAAAGCUUCACUUUCCCUAUAGAGAAAGCAAGCAACAUGAAUCUUCUGAUUUGGGGCCCAGCCUGCUGCUGUAUACAGAGGUUGGCAUUAUUGGUGAUAGAAAUGUCUGAUAGGAGUCUUUUAAUUAUACUCUGGAGUGUGGAGGUGGAGUGCAAGGCUGCUUCCUUUAUUACUGCAAGUGUUAUUUUCUAUUAUCUCAGGUUUCGUUUUGUGUAAUAAACUGCUUCUUGUUAAACAA